UUUUUUUUUUUCUGAGACAGAGUCUCGCUCUGUCGUCCAGGCUGGAGUGCAAUGGCGCUAUCUCAGCUCACUGCAACCUCUGCCCCCCGGGUUCAAGCGAUUCUCCUGCCUCAGCCUCCUGAGUAGCUGGGAUUACUGAUGCACAUCACCACGCCUGGUUAAUUUUUUGUAUUUUUAGUAGAGAUGGAGUUUCACCAUGUUGGCCAAAUUGGUCUCGAACUCCUGACCUUGCGAUCCACCCACCUCAGCCUCCCAAAGUGCUGGGAUUACAGGCGUGAGCUACCACGCCCAUCCCGUGUCAGGUCUUUUACCUUAAUUAAUACGUAUUGUAUUGACAAAUUUUCUUUUCUUUCUGAGCCCUCACUUUUUUUUUUUUUUUUGAAACAAGGUCUCACUCUGUUGCCCAAACUGGAAUGUAGUGAUAAUGAUCACAGCUCACUGCAGCCUCAACCUCUUGGGCUCAAGCUAACCUCCCACCUCAGCCUCCCAGGUAGCUGGGACUACAAGCACAUGCCACUACACCUAAUUUUAUUUUACUUUUUGUAGAGAUGGGGUCUCCCCAUGUUGCCCAGACUGGUCUCGAACACCUGGCCUCAAGUCAUCCUCCUGCCUCAGCCUCCCAAAGCACUAGGAUUAUAGGCGUGAACCACCCUGCCCGGCCAUGAAGUUAAAUUUUUGGUUAUUAGCUUGUUGAGUUCUGUUUUCUGUUUUUUUAAAUAGCCACAUGGCCUGACUCUCUGUGGUCAAUGGUAUGGAUGCUAAAGUAGAGCAAGGACAGUGCCCUGCUCAAGUCUCUCUGACCUGGGUCCAUGGGGAUUUUCUCUGCCAGUCAGGUUCCUGAAGCUCUGGCUACGGCUCCUGGUAUUUUUAAUGACCGCAGUAGAGAAAAACAUUGGUAUCUUCUUGCUGUUGAUGAGCAAAUCUUUGGACCUGUCUCAUGGUGUCUUUAUUUGCAAACUGGUUGAAUCAUGAACUGCCUGGCUUUGGCUGCCUUGCCGUUGUGGCUUUUAAUAACUACCCCUAUUUCUGGUGGCUCAGUCAAGUUUCCAAAAAGGAAGUCUUACCUGGAGAUCCUGUGAAGGAAUUCCUGACCAGCUUUUUAAUUUUCCAAAGACAGGCCUUAUUCGUGUUAAACACACACCCCUUUUCUGUGGCCAGGCCGGUGUGAAAGCAUGUGCAGAGGCUGUAUAGCAGUAAGAGUUCCCACCCCUUGGGGCAUUUUCAUUGUCACCACAUUGUCUGACUUUGGAGACGACCCCUUUUAAACUCUGGCAUUUGCUCAGGUCCACCUGGGCUUGCGAAGGCACAGAUUCCCCGUCCACAGCUCACGACCAGAUGCACCAGCAGGAGUCCACAUCGAGGACGUCCUCCGGGCACUCCCACGACCAGAUAAGGAAACUGAGGCACAGUUCAGUCAAAGCACAUGUCCUGGUCACACAGCUAGGGAGGUGCAAGCCUGCCCGCCCAGAGCCCAUCUUCACUCCGGUGACCAGGAGUUAAACUUUGGGAUGUGCCCGUGAUGUUGGACCACAAGGACUUAGAGGCCGAAAUCCACCCCUUGAAAAAUGAAGAAAGAAAAUCGCAGGAAAAUCUGGGAAAUCCAUCAAAAAAUGAGGAUAACGUGAAAAGCGCGCCUCCACAGUCCCGGCUCUCCCGGUGCCGAGCGGCGGCGUUUUUUCUUUCAUUGUUUCUCUGCCUUUUUGUGGUGUUCGUCGUCUCAUUCGUCAUCCCGUGUCCAGACCGGCCGGCGUCACAGCGAAUGUGGAGGAUAGACUACAGUGCCGCUGUUAUCUAUGACUUUCUGGCUGUGGAUGAUAUAAACGGGGACAGGAUCCAAGAUGUUCUUUUUCUUUAUAAAAACACCAACAGCAGCAACAAUUUCAGCCGAUCCUGUGUGGACGAAGCUGCUGUGUCGGGGGCCAACGGCAGCACGCUCUGGGAGAGACCUGUGGCCCAAGACGUGGCCCUCGUGGAGUGUGCUGUGCCCCAGCCAAGAGGCAGUGAGGCACCUUCUGCCUGCAUCCUGGUGGGCAGACCCAGUUCUUUCAUUGCAGUCAACUUGUUCACAGGGGAAACCCUGUGGAACCACAGCAGCAGCUUCAGCGGGAAUGCGUCCAUCCUGAGCCCUCUGCUGCAGGUGCCUGAUGUGGACGGCGAUGGGGCCCCAGACCUGCUGGUUCUCACCCAGGAGCGGGAGGAGGUUAGUGGCCACCUCUACUCCGGCAGCACCGGGCACCAGAUUGGCCUCAGAGGCAGCCUUGGUGUGGACGGGGAAAGUGGCUUCCUCCUUCACGUCACCAGGACAGGUGCCCACUACAUCCUCUUUCCCUGCGCAAGCUCCCUCUGCGGCUGCUCUGUGAAGGGUCUCUACGAGAAGGUGACCGGGAGCGGCGGCCCGUUCAAGAGUGACCCGCACUGGGAGAGCAUGCUCAAUGCCACCACCCGCAGGAUGCUUUCCCACAGCUCUGGAGCAGUGCGCUACCUGAUGCAUGUCCCAGGGAACGCCGGUGCAGAUGUGCUUCUUGUGGGCUCAGAGGCCUUCGUGCUGCUGGACGGGCAGGAGCUGACGCCUCGCUGGACACCCAAGGCAGCCCAUGUCCUGAGAAAACCCAUCUUCGGCCGCUACAAACCAGACACCUUGGCUGUAGCCGUUGAAAACGGAACUGGCACCGACAGACAGAUCCUGUUUCUGGACCUUGGCACUGGAGCCGUCCUGUGUAGCCUAGCCCUCCCGAGCCUCCCUGGGGGUCCACUGUCCGCCAGCCUGCCGACCGCAGACCACCGCUCAGCCUUCUUCUUCUGGGGCCUCCACGAGCUGGGGAGCACCAGCGAGACGGAGACCGGGGAGGCCCGGCACAGCCUGUACAUGUUCCACCCCACCCUGCCGCGCGUGCUGCUGGAGCUGGCCAAUGUCUCUACCCACAUUGUCGCCUUUGACGCCGUCCUGUUUGAGCCAAGCCGCCACGCCGCCUACAUCCUUCUGACAGGCCCGGCAGACUCAGAGGCACCCGGCCUGGUCUCUGUGAUCAAGCACAAGGUGCGGGACCUUGUCCCAAGCAGCAGGGUGGUCCGCCUGGGUGAGGGUGGGCCAGACAGUGACCAAGCCAUCAGGGACCGGUUCUCCCGGCUGCGGUACCAGAGUGAGGCGUAGAGGCACGCCAGCCAGAGCCUGUGGAGAGACUCCGCCUGCUGACACUAAACGUCCUGGGAAGUGGGCCCUUCCCUGGGUCUCUGCACUGACUCCCCCACUCCUGACCCUGGUGAUGGUCGCCACUGGGCAGCAGCAGCCUUACCAGUCCUCCAUGAUCACACCCAGGGACCUGCAUGGGUGAGGGGACACCCUGGGCCUCUCUCCCGCCCAGCAUCCUCCCUGAGUCCCCACACAGGGCCUCACUCUGCACCCCACCAGGGUCCCGCUCACACCAGGCAGCCUUCAUAGUGGUCUCCCUGGCCACCUUGGGCAGAGCUGGGUCAUGCAGCACCCCAUCCUUACCCGGUGCCCUCUCCUUGCCAGCUUCUCCCCAGGCCAGAGCGGCCAUCGCGUAGAAAGAACCAGGGUGUCCCCGGGACAGGCCGUCCCCCACCCCAUCCUGUAGAAGUCCAUUCCCCUUUUCCCUCCUGUGCUCUGUCCCCCAAGGAGUCAUGGAACUCAGGGUACUGGGCCUCAACGGGAACCUGAGACAGCUCCAGCUUCGCAGCCCUUCCCGGAGCUACAGGGGGAUCCUCUAGCAUGGGGGGUGUGACUUGGUUCCUUUGACCAGGUCCUGUGAGGAAGCCUGGAGCAAGGGUCUCCCCCAGCAGGAUGGGUGGGGCCUGCUCUGGAGCUGAGCCCGUGGCCGCUCACAGGUGUCCUUAGUGGUGUUGCAGCUGUCUACUGGCUGCAUGUGCUGUGAAUAUCCCAAGGAACUGGCUGUGGAAUGCGUGUUUGGGUCAGUCUGUGCCCUCUCAGUAGACACUGGAGCUGCUCUGUCCCUGAAGAGGCCCCGUGCCCCAGGCAUGGCAAGCGCCUGCCUCUCCCCUUCCGGUGCUCACACGCCCACGCCGUGCCACCCGAUGCAGGACUCACCUCUGUGCCUUGCUGCUCCUGAGGCCCAAGGGCAGCCAUGGUGCUCUGUACUGCUCGGGCCGCCCAGGUCACAGAGCCUGAGCUUCGUAGCCAAAGCAGCCUGAUGACCCACCCACCAAGGAAGAAAGCAGAAUAAACAUUUUUGCACUGCCUGAAAAA